AUGUGGACACUGGGAGAAGGAAGUGAGAUGGAAAAGUUCUUUGAUUGCAUCCAAGAAGUGAAUGGUCCUCAAGGGCGACCAUUGGCUGGGUAGUGGAGUGUUGACCAAUCACAGCUCAGGGGCGUGAUUGUCUCGUCCUGGGAUCGCGAGAGGGGUAUAUACAGGGAGGCCAGGCAGCCUGGAGUUAGCCGACCGUUGCGAGACGUUGAGCUGCGGAAGAUGAGUCCAAAGCCGAGAGCCUCGGGACCUCCGGCCAAGGCCACGGAGGCAGGAAAGAGGAAGUCCUCCUCUCAGCCGAGCCCCAGUGACCCGAAGAAGAAGACUACCAAGGUGGCCAAGAAGGGAAAAGCAGUUCGUAGAGGGAGACGCGGGAAGAAAGGGGCUGCGACAAAGAUGGCGGCCGUGACGGCACCUGAGGCGGAGAGCGCGCCAGCGGCACCCGGCCCCAGCGACCAGCCCAGCCAGGAGCUCCCUCAGCACGAGCUGCCGCCGGAGGAGCCAGUGAGCGAGGGGACCCAGCACGACCCCCUGAGUCAGGAGGCCGAGCUGGAGGAACCACUGAGUCAGGAGAGCGAGGUGGAAGAACCACUGAGUCAGGAGAGCCAGGUGGAGGAACCACUGAGUCAGGAGAGCGAGGUGGAAGAACCACUGAGUCAGGAGAGCCAGGUGGAGGAACCACUGAGUCAGGAGAGCGAGGUGGAGGAACCACUGAGUCAGGAGAGCCAGGUGGAGGAACCACUGAGUCAGGAGAGCGAGAUGGAAGAACCACUGAGUCAGGAGAGCCAGGUGGAGGAACCACCGAGUCAGGAGAGCGAGAUGGAAGAACUACCGAGUGUGUAGACGGCCAAGUACUCCCCUAUCUCCGAGAGCAGCGACUAAGUUCAGGCCCAGCCGCCAGACCUCAGAGAUCUCACCAGCGGGGUGCUUGCCAUUCUGAAGAUAAUAAAAUGAAUGUGUUGCAAAUUGA